GUUUUUGAGCGUCUACUACCGUUCCGGGGAAGUGCAGUGCCCGCGUUUUGCUUGGGGAAUUUCAGACACCGGCAUGGGGAGGACCCACGGGCAGAACCCGAGGGAGUAAUUUUGCAAAUCCAAGAUUUUUUGGAACUUCUAUAAUUUUGUUUUCGUGUGUCCUCUUUUUAGAAUCGAGAAACCAGAGAUAUAUUUUUAACAUUACAAAUCAGAAGAAUUUGCUACGGAGGAAAAAAGUAUGCUUUUAGCAGUGUUUUUCCCCUAUUUAUUUUUUUAAUUACAAAAGUACUGCUUGCUCCUUGAGAAAAACAUGAAGCAGCCAAACAAUGAGGAAACCUGCCCUCUCUCGCGCCCUUCCCCCCAUAUUUCUCCUUCUUACUACCCAGGGUAGCCAGUCUCCAAGUGUGGUGGGUAGUUAUUCAGGAUUUUUUUUUUCUGUGCAUUUAAUGAGUGUGCUUUAGAAACAAGAUUGGGAUCAUAUAUAGUACAGUAUAUCGUUUUAUUAGCCAACAAUGCAUCAUGGAUAUUCCUCCAUUUUAUUACACACCUCAUUAUUUUAAAAAACAUUAUUACUAUGUAUUAGAGAAUCCAAUCUACGUAGGCUUGGGGAAGCCUUUUCUUCAUUGUUAAACAUGGUCGCCAAGUUUUCAAUAAUCAGUAGCUUUGAAAAGGGCUACAAGCCAAUAUUUUGAAACAAUGUGGCAAAACUUUCAGAAUGUCUGCGGCCAGACGACAUUACUUUCGUAUUAAGCAGAUUAAUAUGUUUACGUAUUGCUUAAUGGUAGUUUACAUGAGGCUAGAUGACUCCAUAAAACAUAAAGUUGCUGAAUUAGUUUACUUUUUGGUUUUUUUUAUUUCAUUUUUUUCUAAGUAAAUUUUAAUUCCAUAUGGUCAGUUGAACACUUGUAAUUUCUUUAACAUGAAGUAGCUAAUAUGUGAAGGAAAGGUAAGGUAGGAAAGAUAGAAAGCUAGUGGCCCUAGCCUGAGACAAGAAAAAAAAAGCAACAGGGAUUAAAUAUUUUGGUAAGUAAGCUAUAGGGAGUAAACUGGAAGUGGAGGGGUGAUACUACACUGCCUACUAUUAAGUAAGACAGAAAGCUAGGAAAUUCCCAUUGCAUACUGUAUUUCUGUGUGCAGAAGAGCUGGAGGCUUUGUUGAUUUAAUCACUAGCUUGUAUUUAUUAAAAAUGUACUGUGUUCAUCUUGGUGCUAGCUUCCAGGGAAAGAACAACUGAGGAAGAUAAUCACGAACAACGUCUGGUUCUAAACAUGCAUAGCCUGAAAUUUUAAGCCAAAUUGUGUAGUAUUUUAUGAUUUGGAAACUGUGCUCGAAAGGAAUAAAAAAAUCCAUGACAUUUUAGUUAUUUUUGGUAAUAAUAUGCUCAUAUAUUUCUCAUAACAACAUAAAUGACAUUCUUCUCAUUCUAUAGAGUAAUAAAUAGAGGCUUUGAGUAAAAGAACUGCUCAAGAUCCCAUUGCUUUUUUUUUUUUUUUGUAAUAGUGCGUGUUUAUAUUCAGGAGUGCUUAAUCCAAGAACCUGUGUUUUCUGCUCUUGUUUUACCUCCUAUGAACGAAAAAUUGUUGCCCUUACGGUUUUUUCUGCUUUCUUUGAAAUGUUCCUUACAGAAUAACUACAUGAAUGUAAUCACAUGCAUUUAAAAUAGUCUAGAGAAUAUAGUGUGAAACUAUAAUGGUAUUUUUUUAGAUGAGGUUUCUGGUGGCAUAUUACUAAAAUUUUAAACUCCUUGAUCUUAUGCUGUUAACCAAGAAGAUGGGGAUUUGUGUUACUUUAGACACUGCUGGGUGCCAUGGUAAAUUGGGAUGUUAUUGUAAAUUGUAGCUCUCACAGCUGCGUAUUGCUUACAAACUCGGAAGGAUAGUCUCAUAUCAGUAAACAUUUUUAUGAACGUAGUUGAACUUUUUUGUAAAUUAGUGUGCUGGAAAGAAUACCAAGAGGGCCCUAAAAAAGUCUAAAAGGAUUAAAAUUUACUUAUGUAAUUAUUGGUAUUUUAAAAUAUUUGGUAGUCACUUAAAAUGCAUAAUGACAGACAAUAGGGUGUCAUAAUAUGGUUUAUUAAUCUUUUUUCAUUUUCCACUAGAUGUGGCAACUACAUAGUUGGAAGAAAUGUGGCGGCCGGGGGCAGUGGCUCACGCCUGUAAUCCUAGCACUUUGGGAGGCUGAGGCAGGUGGAUCGCCUGAGGUCAGGAGUUCGAGUCCAGCCUGGCCAACAUGGCAAAACCCCGUCUCUACUAAAAAUACAAAAAUUAGCCGAGCUUGGUGGUGGGCAUCUGUAAUCCCAGCUACUCGGGAGGCUGAGGCAGGAGAGUCGCUUGAACCUGCGAGUCAGAGGUUGCAGUGAGCCAAGAUCGCUCCACUUCACUCCAGCCUGGUCAAAAGAGUGAGACUCUGUCUCAAAAAAAAAAAAAAAAAAAAAAAAAGAAAUGGGACAAAUACUAACAUUAAUAAAGUAUGGUCAGUUGUAAUCUGUAUUUGAGAAGAAACCAAAAAUACAGGAAAAGCUUUGACAUUUUACUGGCAAUUGUUAAGGAUGAUAAUUGGAUUCAUACCUAAAUGGCGUAUCUGCCAUUGAUUAUCUCUCGGUCAACGUAACAUUGGAUGUUGGAUGUGAGUGGGUUUUAUAAUUAGGUGACACAGAAAUAUUUCAGCCCCCUAAAGACGUUUUUAGAAUAUGGUAAGAUUUUUUCAGCUGUUGAAGUGGGGAAGGAUUGUGAAUCAAACACUAUGUGUAUGUGUAUUCUCAAAAAUUAAUGAGAGGUAUUGCUGAUGGGAAGACAUAGCAUAUUUUCCAGUUUAACCUGAAAAUCCUUUUUGGAACAUUAUGCACGGGUAGCCAGAAAUAACUCAACUUUAUGUCUUGAUACAAGACAUGCAUCAGGUAUGAUUUCUAGAGCUUAAAAUAUUCUUGGAGUUUAAAAACUAAUUUGCAUAAAACACUCUUCUGUGUUUUCUACUGAGCACUCUUCAGUAACUUGCAGGCUCUUAAAAACCUUUAAUGAUAAUCAUGUUAUCAAUUGAUGAAGUCAGUUCAGUUUAUAAUCUAAAGUUAUAAUGAGCAUUGAAAGAGCUGUAGAAUGUGAAAUGCUGUGAAGGUCUGUCUUGGUGACUUUCACAAACUGGCAUCUCCAACUCUCCCUUCUUGGGGCCUUUGUUUGUUUUUCUCUCUCACUUCCUGAAGUAUAGAUAGAUGUUGCCUGUAGGUGUUACCUUAGGUUUAGUUCUUUUCCUUUUUAGAGUUUGUUCUCUUCUUUGGCAAUCCCACACAGAUCCGUGGUUUCAACUGCUCAUUCCCCUCACCCUCUUUGCUCAGGCUUCCACUUGUGUAUCAUCAGCCUUAUUUUCAUUCCCAAGCUUCAGAUUUGCCAAUGUUGUUCUCCCUGAUCAACUUAGUAGCUGUCAUUUUGUAAUCUUGAAUCAGUAGAUUCAGAAUUAAACUUUUUUUGCAAGCCUGAUUCUUCUUGCUUGUUUAUAUUAAUGACCUUUGCAUUUUCUUAGUCAUCUAGACUCAAAAUCAAAAGGUCAUCCUUGGUUCUUCUCUCUCUCCUUUUCUUAGAAUUUUUUUUUUUUUUGUCAUCUUACUGCAUUGUGGUUCCUGAUUUCUUCUAUCUUUCUUCAGUUCUUCCAGCAGCCAUAUACACAGCAAGAGACAUUAAUCUCUAGGUUUGUCAUUCAUUGUGAAUACUGCUUAUUAAUUGUCCUAAAUGUAGUCCUGAUCAUGUUCCCUGCCUGAUGACAAGCAAACAAAACAAACCCACUUGGGUGUUUAUGUCAGUCAGUGUGCUGAAUCCUUUGUUCUCAUGUGGUCAUUAUAAUUUAUAUUAUCCCCAUUCUACAGGUGAAGAAAUUGGAACUUCAUGAUCUUGAAGGAGUUGUUAGUAGGUAGAAGAGCUCUGGGAUUUGAAUCCCAACCAUGUCUUCUUCCAAGUCUGUGUUCUUGACCACUGUGCCUCUGCUGAGUGGCUCCUGAUCCACUCUGGAAGAAAGCCCGAGUUCCUCAGUGUUGCCUUUCAAAACUGCAUUAUUUGACUUCAGUGCCCCUUUCAAAACUUAUUUCUUGUUUUAGUUUAAAAUAUUAAGUUACAUUCUUUCUGUCCCAGCAGCUGUUCCAAAAAGAAUGUAAACUUCAGUUUUACUUUACUUUUUUGAUUUCUUAUGCAUUUCCAUUUCUUGGAAUUUUUUUCUUUCUCCCAUCUCUGCCUUUAGAAGUCUUCCAUGUAAAAGUCUAGUUUAUACAGCGUACACCGUAUUUCCCUAGAGCCCCCACCUCCCAGUCUGUGUAGUACAGUAGUAAAAUCUCCUGCACAUUCAUACAGCUGUUUAACCUGUGAUGAUACUUUGUACUCUAAAUUUGUUUUGAGUACUCUAACAGUUGUAAUUGGAUUAUAUAAGAUGCUUGAAGCACAAACUAUGUCUUACUGUUCCUUGUGUCUUCCAGUGGGUGCUCAGGAAGUAUGGGUAAAUAAGUAUGAAAAUGAUCACUGGUAAACUACCCCUUUCAUUGGUAUUUAAGCAGUAUAUUUGAUUUUAGUUUCUCUCUCUCUGUCACACACACUAGCUUGUUUGAGUUUUUAAUUGUGUGUGUCCACAACAGAACUAAAUUUCUUGUUGUAGGCUAUCAUGAAUUGUUUUCAGAUUAUAAGGUAAUUAUAUUGUUUAUUUAAGACAAAUCAGUUUUGUCUUUCCAUGUGCACAUAUCCUUUCUUGGUACUGUAUAUAAAUUUUUAAAAAAAUUAAUGAUUUAGUAUUUGAAUUAUUUUCCAUGCUGUUGAGUCAGACAAGUUUUCUAAUGAGCUGCAAUAUUCUCAUAAACUCUCUGAUCUUACAGUUUCUUUAAGCUUGCAUAGAUGUGAAAGAUGGAGUACAACUCUGUCUAUACUUUAGUAUUGUUUUCUUCCUUUUGGUGAUAUCAGGAAGCUCCAGCUGUACAAUCAGCUGAAAUGCCCUCACACAGAUUAUACAUAAUUCUUACAUUGCUGAAGAGUUCAUAUGAAAUUUCAGACUUUUUAAAAAUAAUCUAUCGAUGUUAAUGGUUAUCAUGCAGAAGUUACAGUUUUUUCUUAUAUCUGCCAUUGUGCCCUGUAUUGUUUAUAGUUUAUCUAACUAAUAAGUAAUUAAUUCUUGCUUUAUAAAGUAAAAAUAUAAUUCUGUUAAGAAUUUUGAAUGUAGGAUAUCUUGGUGAUGGGAAGAGACGUUUUCUUUUUGGAAUGUUAAAAUGCAUGCUUAUAAAGGAAUGAGACUGAUUCUCAAACUAAUCCAUUUGUAGUCUACCUGCCCUUAGCUUUAUAAAAUAUUAAAGUAAUCAUAAAUACUUCUUUGAAGAUACAAAUUGUAAGUGAGCUUAAAAUAAUUCACUGACUUUAAAAAUAGUUAAUAUAUCACAUGUUGCAAAUUUUAAGUGAUACAAAAAAUAUAUAAACUGAAAAUGUAUCUUCCUCAGCCUCCCAUUUUCCCCCCUGGGAUGGGAAGUAGUCACUUACCUCUGGAAUGAUAUAAUGGAAACUAUUUUUUUAUUUGUAUGUACAAUGAAAUAUAAAUAAAUUUUCUUUCCACUUACAUAAAGAUGAGGUACACUGCUGUUUUUUUCACUUGGAUUUUCACAUAACCAUAUAUCUCUAUGAGGAGAUAAAGAACCACUUCAUUCUUAAAAAAACAAUUUCAGCCUCAGAGUAUAUUAUAGAUAGCUACAGCUAUAGAUUGUAUUUCAAUUAUAAUUGAUUUAACUAUAUUCCCUACUAAUGAGCAUUUAGUUUCUAACUAUUACAACCGUUGUGACAACACUUUGAAGGAAGAAAAGUAAAAAGUAGGUGGUCUUUUCUUGUAGGGGAAAAUAAAGUUUGAAAGCUGAAAUGGGCUUUUUGGUUCCUUUUCUGACCUGAUGAUUAGUGUGUAAGUGAAUGGAGAGAACUGUGGGGUUAUGUGAAGACAUUUGCUAGAAGCCAUAGUUGACAAUCGAGUUGGAAGAGUUGGGAUGGUAGUGGUGAUGGGUAGCAGCUGCCAUGACCAAUGGUCCACUCUGGGCAAGGGUCAGCCCUGCAUGUGUUAGCAGUUCAGUGUUUAGAAAUGAUACGUGGUAUCUGGAGUUUGGUGUCUGGAUCUAUGGCCUAUGCUAGUAUAUUUAACGUAGGAAACCUAUGCAGGGGAUGAAUUUAGAUCCCUUUGUGUCAUCUAGAAGGAAAUGUUGUGGCUUACAAUAUUGUAUGUGGUUAUUAAUCUUUUUAUUGAAAAAUUAUUGUAUAUUCAGAAAUAAGAUUUAAAUUACUAAAUUAAAUGGAGUUAAACAAGCAGGCCCCCAUCAUCUGUGUCUGCUCCUCAUGGUUUGCUGGGGUAAUGGUUUUUUAACAGUUUGGUAUGAAUGCUUUCAGACUUAUGUAUAAACAGAAACAAUAUAUUCGUGCAUAUUAAAAAUGUCAGUCAGAAUUCUGUUGAAUAACAAGUACAUGGAAUGAAUGGUAAAAGUCAGAAUCUUUAACAAGAGAAGAAGGUGGUGGUGGGAUACCAGGUAAUUAUAUAGUGAAUGUUCUUUGAUUCCUUUAGAUCCAAGGGGGCUGUAAAUACACACUGUUAAUUGUGUAAACUGUACUACCUAUUUAGCCUCUGUAGCUAGUUUAUCAGGUUAUUUCUACAGAUCAUUUAAGGUUUCUGAAGCUAUAUAUAUAUAUAUACAUAUAUAUGUAUAUAUAUAUUUUUUGUUUUUUUUUUUAACUAGUGGCAUAUAAUUUACUGAAUAAUGAUAUAUUCUCUUUAUUUUCCAGGCAUUCUAUGCUAAAUUUGGGAUUUGAGUGUUUUUUUGUUUUCUUUUUUUUGAGACAGGGCCUCGCUGUGUCACCCAGCCUGGAGUGCAGUAGUGCGAUCUCGGCUCACUGCAUCCUCCACCUCCUGACCUCGAGCAAUCCAACCUCAACCUCACCAGUAGCUGGGAUUACAGGCAUGUGCCACGAUGCCCGGCUAAUUGUUUUUUUCUUUCAUUUUUUGUAGAGAUAGGUGUCUCAGUAUGUUGCCCAGGCUUGUCUCAAAGUCAUGGGCUCAAGCCAUCCUCCUGCCUUGUCCUCCCAAAGUGGAUUAGAGGAGAAAGCUACCUUGCCCGGCCUCAUGUCAUUUAUUUUUAGGGUGGUAUGUGUAUGCUGCCUAGGUUCAUAUGGUUUAGAUUUAUUUUUAACAGUGGUUCAUUUGCACUGACCCAUUUCUGAGCUCCUGCGAUUCUCUUUGGUCAAUUAUACUUCCCUAGAUAUUGUGAACAUAAUAAGUAAAAGCUCAUUUAUUUGAUUUUGCUUUUUUCCCUGUAUAACAGCAGUAGAAAUUUAUUGUGGAAAGACUAGAAAAUAUGGAUAAAGAAAAGGAGAAACAGGUUAACGGGGAUGUUAUCACCUGAGGCUCGUAUGGUUUUUAAUUCUGAGGGACCUCUGUGUUAAUGAAAACACCACUAGAAAUGUCCAGCUUUGUAAGUCCUUCUGCCAUGUAAUCCUGUGGCAGAUGUAUUUGGUGAUAGAAGUAUGGAAAAUGUGAGUGCUUGCAUUUUCUCUGACCUGGAUGCAUCUGUGCUAGGAAGUGGUGUUUUAAGUAACCAAGGUUGUGUUAAGGCCUUGACUUAAUGUUAUUAGGGGAUUUCUACAUUUAUACUGCCAAGCACAUGGGUGUUUAGCUGUUGGUUAUGGGAGCCACAGGUGUGCUGGUGGAUGGAUCAGUCGGUGCUUCUCUGUCACUGCUACUGCGUAAGUAGUGCAGAGGUUUUGUUCUGAUUAUGUAUCAUUAUAUCUUUGUAGUCCAUAUUUAAAAUACUGGGCCUUGAGUAGAAGGAACUAUUUAGAAAUGUCAUAGCUCAAAAAGCAAAUGCAAAACAGUCUUUGUUUUAGAAGGAUGGUUUAUCCCUGUUACUCCUGUAAGUCUCGGUAUUCUAAAUUUUCAUGUUUUCAUUGUAGUGUCUUGGCGGCUAGAGCGGAUUUUAAAUUUUCUGGUCAGUCUUCAUACUCAACUGGAUAAGAACAAAUUUUGGAACAUGCAAAGGCAGUCACUCUAAUUUUAGUUUCAAGGAAAAGCCUAGCAGUGAUAUAUACUGAUUUACCAGGCAUUGUAAAUCCCAUUGUGAAAGAAUUAUUUUAAAUACAUCUAAACCGUUUUUAAUAGGCUUGACUUUUCCCUGUAAAUAGAGUAAUUUGAACCUUUAUUCUUUUAUGAACCAGAGAAAUUAGAAAUAGAUGUAGGCAUUUCUACAAUGAUCUAUAUAAAUAUCUGUGAAUAUAACCAUUCAUGCAGUUGAUUUGGCUUUAAAGAAAAGGGAGGUAAUCACCAUGGACUUAAAGUAGUUUAAUUACCUCAUUAUUUAUGACAAAAAGGCUUUAUAUAAGCUUUUUUUUUUUUUUUUGUUAAGGACUUGUUCAGUUAUCACUGUUUAGUUAUCACUGGUUUUAUUGUAUCUAGGCAGCACAAUAAAAUUAAUUCACUUCACACUAAUAUAUAUUUUUGUGUGUACACACACACACACACACACACACACACGUAUAUCCUUACAUAUGGCCAUUUGUGGUGCACAGCUCAGGAGACACUAUUAACAUAGAAUCUAAUAUAAAUGACAUUCCCUUUACUGCUUCAGGAAAACUGACACUUUAUGUGGGAAUAGUGCUUCCUGGCAUUGUGUAGUCAGCAUGAGACCCUGUUAAAUUUGAUACUUUCCACAUUUUCACAUUUUCGUAUAACUUUGCAUCUUGUCAAAGAGGUAGGAAAGUAUUGUUAUUCCCAUUUUAUAGAUGCAUGAACUAAGACUCAGAAUGACUUCAGUUUCCUCAGUCUGCUUUAUUUUCUAUAAAAUGAUGAUACCAGACUCAGCAAUCAACAGUGUUGAGGGACACAGGGUUUGGUGUCAGAUAGAUCUAGAACUCAACCUCAGUUUUGCCUCCUACUAGCUGUAAAAGCUUAAGGAAGUUAUUUAAUCCCUUUCCUUCGUUUCCCAUCCCUAAAAAUAAUGCUGUUACAUGAAAUUUUAUGAAGACUUAAAUGAGUUAAUAUACUUAAAACACCUCAAAGCUUUAUGCUGUAAGUGCUCAAUUAAUGAUAGUUGCAUUAAUAAUCAGUAAUAAAGGUUAUAUAUUAUUUUGUGAGUCGUAUACUACUUUUCAGAGAUUAUGAGGUCAGUUAACACUUGAUAGAAAGUGACGGACCUAACCUAGAAGCAAUAUCCGUUUUAAGUAGAGGCCAAACUUGGACUGAUAACCUCAUGCUCUCUUACCAAUAUUGUAGGCAGUGAGUGAGGAGUUAACAAUAACAACAAAAGGCCUAGGAAAAGCAAGGAGAAUGUGUCCUAUAUAGUCAGGGACAGACUUUGGAGUCACACUAGACCCACCAUAGUUGUGUGUAAAAUAAAGCAGAUUUGAAUCAUCUAGUCACACAAAAAAGAAACGAGAAGUUACUGCAGUGAGAGAGCAAAGCAGUUCCAGAUGGUGGAAUGCUUUUACUGUGUGUGUUGGUCUCUGAGGUGCUCGUGACAUACCAUUAUCAUACUGUUCCUCAUAAUGACCCUCAGCCACUAAGAAAUGGUUGAGUUAUGCGGGAUAAUUUGCUAAGACUGUAGAACUAAUACACUAUAUAAAGACUUUCAUUACUUUGUUUUUAAUCUUUGCAACUUAAAGGAGUAUUUUUCAGUUACCAGUAACAUUAAUUUGUUUUACUCGGUGCUAGAUAAAAAUGACUAAAUUUGAAUGUGCACAUUAUUUCAUUUGAUUCUUAAAACUAAGUAGGUCAUAGAAAGGUUAAUGGCCAAUGGUAAAAUAAAGGCUAUGAGUUCAGACUUUCAUGCAUAUAUUUGAUUCUGGGUCUCUUUCUCAUUGUUAACCCAAAGCUUAUUUAUAAAGGUCAGGGCCUGCUUGUUUGUUUUCAUACCCUUUAGUGCCUUCUACUGUGGGAGCAUUACGAAAAUCAGGUCCUGCUCCUAAAUGUCUUAAUAUUUUGUUAUCUAGUGUAUCUUCCCAUUCAUUUUUUUGUGAUACACAAAAGUCAUUUACCUGAAGGGGAAUCUAUUUUUAAAAGGAUGCUCCCUCUUGAGGCCAACCUGGAAUCCUCCUGCAUUGAAUUGACAAUUUUGAAUCUGCUACUAUAUCCUGUUGGAUGUCAACAGCUAAGGAAAGGUAUGGACCAUCAUAUACAGGGUCUUACUCUAUUGAACUGAACUUCUGUAAGCACUCAGAAUGAAUCUAUAUGGUAGCUUUCUACUACCCUAAAAGUAAGGUCAGGAGUUAGGAAUGAACUCUAAACAGUUUUAAACUUGAAGUUUAUAUUUAGGCACAGUUUCUUCUAAUAGAGUAAGAUAUUAGAAAUUAUGAAAACUUGGCCGGGCACGGUGGCUCAUGCCUGUAAUCCCAGCACUUUUGGAGGCCGAGGUGGGCGGAUCACGAGGUCAAGAGAUUGAGACCAUCCUGGCCAACAUGGUGAAACUCCGUCUCUACUAAAAAUACAAAAAAAUUAGCUGAGUGUGGUUGGCACGUGCCUGUAAUCCCAGCUACUUGAGAGGCUGAGGCAGGAGAAUCGCUUGAACCCGGGAGGCAGAGGUUGCAGUGAGCUGAGAUCGUGCCACUGCACUCCAGCCUGGUGACAGAGCAAGACUCUGUCUCAAAAAAAAAAAAAAAGAAAUUAUGAAAACUUUUUUGUGAAACUGUUCUCAAAUAUUGGGACUGAGCGUACUCUUUUUUUUUUUUAAUUUAUUUUAAACGAGGAAAAUGAUUGCAUGGCUUGAUAAUUACCAUACCAAAUGAUUGAUAGUUUUGUUUUUUUGCAGUUUCUAGUUGCUACUUAAAAUUGAGUUUCAGGGUGUUCAGUUAGUUUAUACAUAGUUAUUGCUUUAGUUAGAGGAUUUUAGACUAUCUUAAGAAUAUAACCUUGCGUUAUUUACCUGUAAGAGAAAAUAAAUUCCAAGUCUGUCAAGUAAUAAUAAGCAUAUUUCUUCUGCUGAUCCUUUCUGCCAUAUUGUUUCUUCACCUGUAUGCUGGAUGAGAAAUGGGAGAAGGGAUGGAUUUGGGCUGCCGGUAUACAUUUUAAGAUGGAUUGUAUCUGAUUCUCUAUGGAACAGCAUUACCCUGAAGAGUAGGAGUCAAAGUUUGGGUAGUGUGCUAGGCAAAUAGUAGCCCCCCAAAGAGGUCCAUGUUCUAAUCCCUGGAACCUGCGAAUAUGUGACCUUAUAUGGCAAAGGGGAAUUAAGGUUGCAGAUGAAUUAAAGUUGCUAAUCAGUUUAAGAUAGGAAGAUUAUCCUGGAUUAUCCCGAUAAGCCCAGUGUAAUCAUAAGGGUCCUUAAAAAUGGAAGGAGGAGGCAGAGCGAGAGAACCAGAGAGACAGCAGAAAAGGAAUCAGCGUCAUGUUUCUUGCUUUGCAGAUGGAAGAAAGAAAGGGCCAUGAGGCAAGAGAGAAAAAAAAAAAGCAGAUGGACACUAGACACUGAUGCGAGGGAACAGAUUUCUCCUAAAGAACCUUCAGAAAGGAACAGUCUCCCCAACACCUUGAUCUUAACCCAGUGAGACUUGUAUCAUGAAGCCUGUGUCAGACUUCUGACCUCCAGAACUAUCAGAUAAUAAACUUGUGUGGUUUUAAGCCAUUAGGUUUAUGCUAAUUUGCUAUGACAGUGAUAGAAAACUAAUACAGGUAAAUAUACUGUGGCCAUUUGAUUCCUUAUGGAAAUGAUUUCUAAACAGCCUCUCCCCAACAAAAGAUUAAGAUGACAUUUAUAAAACUGAUAAAACUAGUGCAGCUGUGUUUAAAUGGGGGUGGCAUUGAGUCCUGCCAGGUGAGAUUUCUUCCCAUUUUUGUAGAAUCUUGGGGGCACCUGUGGAUUUUUGGAGCUGCUUUCUUUAUUGAUAAAAGUUGUAUACUGGGCAGAUGAAUCAAAAUGGCAUAUAGGAAUCCCAUUGAAAUUGGGAUAACUACAGGUAUGAUCAUCUUGAAGUUCAUUGCAGUAAUCUAGCAAAAAUUGAUAGGGGUAUUGACAAAAGGGCUUUUCACUAAGGGGAAUGGGAGUAAUUAAAGAGUAGCUGGUCUGAAAGGUGAGGGGCUAUAGUUUUAAAUAUUCUAAAUUUGAAAUGAUAGAACUUUCCUCCCCAGUGAAAUUAAUCUAGAAACUUACUGAAUGCACUGGAAAAUUUCAGCUAAAGAGGAUGAUGAUUUUGAAUAAGUCGAACAGGGGAAAGGAAAAAUAGCUGUUCUGAAGUCUCUUCGGCAAUAUGUUGGAGGAAGGGACGAAAUUAACAGCUAUUUAAAUUGCAGAAAAGCAGACAGAAGUUGAGGUCCUUGUGGAUUUGCUGCAAGGAUUCUUACCAGUUUGGAGGAAAGAGCCUUGUGCUUUAAGAAACUGUACAUAGUCUUUGUUCUUAGUAGGAAAGAAUAUCCUUGUGCAUUCACUGUAAGUACACAUUUAAAAAUGCAUUUCCAAUGCUCACUAGUUGUUAAAGGAGAAAUUAUAGUAAUGUCAUUGGAUAACACAAAUUACAAAAAAUUGCUAUCUUUGAAAGUGUUUUUGUUUUUCCAAAACACAUAUAACCUUCUGACCCAGCACAAACAACGUAUGCCCCUGUAGAGACAUAAGGCUGUCUAUCCGACAGUUACCACUCUUCUGUGGUGUUGAGUGUAUUGCAUUUUAAUACAGUGGCAAAGUAUGUGAUUUAUUUAGUGUCAUUUACUGUUGCUUUAUUGUAAAAUUGUUUUUCUGCAGAUAGCUCCUUUGUGAAUUUGUAUUUUUAGUCUGCCUACCUAUGCCUACAUGAAAUUUAAGGAGUUUUUCAGUGGUUUUAUUUUGUCAUUUCCCAUGUGUGUUAAUAAUCAUGUAAGUUUAUAGGAGAGAAGCAAGGGCACCAGAAAGAACAUGUGCUUCAGUUAACAAGUUCUUUUCAAGCCGACUGCAGUAGAUGAAGCCACUAAGGCAUCCUCCUGUCUAAAAGUUUGUAUGAUAUAUUGUCCUAGGCAGGAACUUGAAGAUGGCAGAAUUGGUAACUGCCACCCUCAGUACUCUUAGUCAGGGCUGGCGUCUAACUUCCCCUCUCUGAUCAUUGUGACAGCUCUCUUAACACAGAAAAUGUGGUGACAGGUGUUUAAAAUUUUGCCAAGAAGCGAAGAUAUCCUCCCCGCCCCCCAAUACUUAGAAGUUAAAGUUAAAAGGAUGAGAGAAUGUUUGUGGGAUAUAGUAAUUUAAGUUAAAUUGAGGAGGUUGUGGAUGCUUUAGCCAAGUAUCAGUAUCUGUUGUAUUUUAGUUAAUUUUAUUGCUCAACUGCUGUCUUUAUUUCGGUGGCUUGUGUGUAGUCUUUCUGGUUUUCAGGAUUAUAUAAAUCUGGGUCCAGUCAGGAAAGAGAAAUCAUGCAGUAAUUUGAGCAGAGAAUGUUUAGUGUAAAGGAUUAUUUACUGUAACAGAACCAGUAGGAAGUACAGAGAGUGCUACAGGAUAUAGAAAUAGAUGUUAAGAAACAGCCACUACUUACAGAACUACAAUUGAGCACCCAAAGAAGAGGCCCAUCCCAGGCUGAGAACAGGUCUUGUUGGAGAGGGUACCUCAAUGGCUUAUUGGAUGGCAGAGAAGUUGAUGGAAUUUGCCAGAAAUCUAUCCUCUAGGAUACCAUAGAAAGAUGUUCAUAGAGAGGCAUUUUGCUAGAGGUUGUGUUCUACAAACUGUCCAAAAGAGAGUGCUGGGGAAAGCUGUCUAUUGUCCUGCACUGCAGCAUCCUCGUGCUGGGGAAGCCUGCCAAGCAUUGCACCAGGCCGGGAAACAAAGUCCUUUCCCCUUGCAGUGUUUUCUCCAGUGCUGUCUGCUGAACAUUACCUAUCAGUUGGGAUUGAGACAGUGGGUAUUAAAAAGACUAUUUCUUUGUGCCUAAUCCCUGGUGGGAUCAGGGCAGCAUAUUACUACACUAGGAUUUUCUUGAAGAACAUACUUGUUACUUUAUUCCCUUUUGCCAUUCAGAAACUUUUCUUUUAGGUAAAAUGAUGGUACAUUCCUUUUGACUUAGAGGCCAAUUCCUGCUUUUGUGUUUGAUUGUUCCCAGUCAGCUGAUAGUGGCUAUUUCCUGCUUGCUUCCGGUAUUCUCUCAUACUGAAAUAUAAAAAUGGAGCCAUAGUCCUGGACCAAAUAUUUAGGCACUGCUUGUUUUUACCACACUGACUCAGAUCAGUGGCUCUGUCUAUAGCUUUAAGAGGUACACCUGGUUUAUUUUAAUAAUAUAAGGCUUUAACACUGUCUCAAUCUCAACUGAUAGGUAAUGUUCAGCAGACAGCAACACACCCAAAGAAGGCAUUUUAUCUCAGAAAAUGUCACAUUUUGUAGCUUUUAUUUUAGGAUGUAUUGAAAAGAAACUCAAGACACGGAGCCACAAAUUCUUUCAGUAUGCCCUUGAACAAGUAGUUUUGUCUGAUGCAUGACAGCGAACUAGAUAAUUUUAUGAUUUUCUUUAUAAUUAUUUCUGUUGACCUGCUUUCACAAAUAUCAAAGUGCCUAUUUUGUUUGGGUUUAUUUGCACGGGAAUAUUUAUGAACUAUGUCUUUGUUUUUGUAAAUGCAAAUGGUUUUAAAGUUCUGGAAUGAGGUUUUUAAAUGUCAACAACAUAAUACGACUGAUUUUUACUUGGCCUCAUUUUGUUGCUUUUGUCACAGUAAUUCAACUGCAGAGAAUUCAGAUGCCAAAAAAAAGCUCUUGUAACCUUAUGCUAGCCUAGGUCUGUACAUCAAGGGAAUGAUUUAGAAAAUACACAUACCUUGGUUGUUUUCAGUUUGACUUUCUGAACACGUUUUAAAAAUAUCGGGCAUUUGUCAACCUUUUUGUACCUCCUUAUACUUAAUAAUAUUUAUAAAACUGUUUACUCUUUUGUGAGAUUUACUGUGGUUUAAUAUUGCAUUAAUAAUUAAGAAGAAAAUCUGUUGAAUUUCUUUGCUCUCCCUGUGUUUUUGUGUGUGUCCCUCUAUUAUUAUCUAUAUAUGCAUAUAUAUACAUUUUACUCUUAAUAACAAUCUCCCCACUUGCUAGCCUUAGGACACUGAAGUAUCAACUCUUUCACCUUUAAUGGGAACUGUGGCAUCUGUACUACAGUCUUUGCUACUUAAUUUAAUUCAGGCCAUGGAAAAUUACAAGUUUAAAUACUUUAUAAUCUGAUGAUAAUACUUUUGGUUUCAUAGGUUUUAUUCCAUCUAGCUAUUAUAUUCCUUGUUGAUUUGCUCUCAUUUUGAACUCUGAAGCAUUUACCUUACUUUUUUUGUCUGUUCUUUUUUUUUGAGACGGAAUCUCGCUGUGUCGCCCAGGCUGGAGUCCAGUGGCGCGAUCUCAGCUCACUGCAAGCUCUGCCUCCUGGGUUCACGCCAUUCUCCCGCCUCAGCUUCCUGAGUAGCUGGGACUACAGGCGCCCACCACCACGCCUGGCUAAUUUUUUUUUUUUUUUUGUAUUUUUAGUAAAGACGGAGUUUCACCGUGUUAGCAAGCAUGGUCUCUAUCUCCUGACCUCGUGAUCCGCCUGCCUCGGCCUCCCAAAGUGCUGGGAUUAUAGGUGUGAGCCACUGCGUCCGGCCGUUUUUUAUUUCUUUUUUUUUUUUUUUAAGUAUGCUAUUCAUAACUAAAUUGUAAGCUUUUAAAGACUUGCGUUUUCUCUCCAAUGAAAUAUAAUACCCCAAACAGGCUAUGUUAAUGUCCAGUGGAGUGUAUAAUUUGUCAAGUACAUAGAUAUAUGUCUUCUGUUCUUUUCAUGAUCUUAAAUAACUGAGAAACUACACUCAGUUACUCAUUAGCAGGGAUCUUGAAUAAUAUCUUUGUUAUAAGGCAUUCAACUAAGUGUCAGAAGUAAACAAGUGACUAGCAUAUAGACCCUUACUUUGAAGAGGCCACAGUCAAGUGGGUGGGAAACAGGAUAAUCACUUUGUGGAGAGAUGAUACAGAGAUACAUAGGCGGGUGUUUGAGAGCUUUUGAAAGAAGGUACAGUUAUGAAUUGAAUGUUCAUGUCCCCCUAAAAGUCACGUGUUGAAACCCUGACCGCCCCCUACCCCAUGCCCAGUGCAGCUGUACUUGAAUACGGGGCUUCCGAGGAAGUAAUUAAGAUCAUAAUGGUGAGGCCCUGAUCCAAUAGCGUCAUUUUAAAAAGUGACACCAGAGAGCUCCCUCAUGCUUUUUUGUGUGUACAAAGAAGAGGUCAUGUGAGAACACAGCAAGAUGGUGACCAUCGGCAAGCCAGGAAGAGAGGCCUAGAGGCCUUACCAGAAAGUGAUUCUGUUGGCACUUUGAUCUUGGACUUCUAGCUUGAGAAAAUAAAUUUGGGUUGUUUAAGGCACCCAGUCUAUGGUACUUUGUUAUGACGCCUGAAAAGACUAAGGCUUAUAAGUGUUUUGGGGUUGGACUUAGAGAUUUCUAAGAGGAGGGGGACUCAUUAGUGGCAUCUGAGUGAACAGGGAGAACUUUCUAGGUAGAGACUUAAUGCAUAUGCAAAAACAUGGAUGCUUGAAGAAGUUUAUUGUGGUUAAGGGAACUUCAGCAAAGGCUGUGGGAGGAGAGAUGGCUGGAGGUGCCCCUGAAAUAGUAUUCAGGGCUCAGAUUAGAUAAUGCACUUUUGAAAUCGAAAAAAAUGGAGCCCAGAUAUGAGCAAAGUUCUGUGGCUUUUGACUUACACCGAGGUUUUAAGCCCAGCUCUAAAUUUUUUUCUUUGUAAAAUGGGUAUAAUAAAACCUACCUUGAAGGUUUUUUUGAAGAAUAAUUAAAAGACAAUUCUAAAACAGUUGGUUGAAUGCCAGGCAACUACUAAGUGUAGUAAUUAUUAAUUAAGUUGGACAAAAUCAGAUCUGUUGGGCUCCAAAUGAAGGUUGAACUUACUACACUCUGCCUGUCUGUAGAUGUAAAUAUAGAUGCUAUCAUAUUUGUAAUAUUCUUGUCUAAUGGGAUGGGAUUAGGAUGACAGUCUGGCAAAUUGAGGCGUUUUGUCUUAUGACCUGUUUUUCUGUGGAGGACGAAGAAGGACCCUUGUGGAGCCUAGUCUUGAGGGGUUGUUGGUUGUAGUAGUGGUAAUGAAUUUGCUGUGCAGGUGGGAGCCAGAGGUAAAUAAACACAAGAGAUAUUGCUGGGCAUUAUUGAAAAUCCAGUUAAGCUUGAAGAAUAUAAAUGUUUAGUGGCACCACCAACACAGGCACUGGAUUUCUUUCUUAAGUAACACUUCACAAUAUAAAACAGUCCAUGGAGAAGAGAGAUUAUUGGCUUGUUCCAUGAUCAGAAGUUUGCAAGAUGAGUGAAGCAGAAAGUUAGAAUGAAGGAUUGAGAGUAAUGAAGACUCAGUAAGUGAAGCAGUGUUCGUGGGGUUGAUUUGGGAAGAAGAUGAGAGUAGGUGUUAGCCGGUUGUAGCCCAUGGGCCAAACUUGGACUACUGUCUUUUUUUGUGUGGUCUGCAAACUAAGAAUGGUGUUUACUUUCAAAUGGUUGGAAGACUAUUUUAUGACAUGAAAAUGAUAUGACAUUCCAAUUUUAGUGUCCAGAAAUAAAAUUGUAUUGGAACAAAGCCAUACUCUUUAACUUUUAAGUUGUCUAUAGCUACUUUUGCCUUACAACAGUGGUGUUCAGUAGUUGGGACAGAAACUAUUGCCUGCAAAUCCUAAAAUGUUUAUUAACUGGCCUUUUCAGAAAAAGUUUGCUGAUCCUUGGGGUAGAGUACUAGUGACAUUGACUGUAGUGGCAGACAACAAGCAAAGUAGACAUAAAAUCAGGUCAGAGAAAAAAGUAAGGAUUCAGGUUGGACAAUUGGGUGAUAUAAGUCCUCAGUUAAAGGUGUCAUAGUUGUUCCUUUGGAGAUUGAAAAGGUUGUUCAUGUACGUUGAGGAUGCCCCUGAUUAUGGUAUGAGUUGGGGAGUAGAGAAGACUACAGUAGAGAUGCUAGAGUUCCCAAUAAAGGUGGAAGAGUUGAUAUUUCCUAAGGAUAGGAAGUGGGGGAUUAUUAUUAAUAUGUAAGAAAACAUAGUAAGAGAUGAAAAUACAAAACAUGUUUUCCUAUACCUUUUUCAAUAAGUUUUUUUUAAAAACAUCAUUAUGAAUCUUAUAGGCCUAAAGUUGUCUUUCUAAUUUUGCAUUUUAAUUGCCACUGAGGUUGGGCAUAAUUUCAUAUUUACUGGUGGUUUAGUAAUUCUUCUGGCAAAUACCUAUUGUCUCCUCUGCCCCCCUCCCCUCUUUUUUUUUUCAUUAAAAGGAGACAGGAUCUUGCUGUGUUGCCCAGGCUGGAGUGCAGUGGUGCUAUUGUAGCUCACUGUAACCUCAAACUCCUGGUCCCAAGGGAUCCCCCUGCCUCAACCUCCUGAGUAGCUGGGACUUCAGGUACAUGCCACCACUUUGCCUGGCUAUUUUUUUUUUUAAACUUUUUUUUUUUGGUUAGAGAUGAUGGUCUCGCUAUGUUGCCUAGGUUGAUCUCUAACUCCUGGCCUCAAGCAAUCCUCCAGCCUUGGCAUUCCAAGGUUCUGGGAUUAUAGGCAUGAGCCACUGCACCUGGCCUUUGCCCUUUUAUUAAAAAAAUUAAAAAUGUUUCUUUGUAAAUAAUUCUUAUAAAUUUGGCUAUCAACCCUUUGCCACAUGUUGCAAUUUUUUCCCCCAGUUUGGUUUUUGUAUUUUGAUGUUUUACUGUGUGCUUUGCCAGAUAGAAUACAUCAUUUUUAUCAUUUUUACGUUUUGCCUGUGGCUUUUUAAUUUAGAAUGUCUUCUCUACCUGAAAUGAGAUACAUAGUUGUCUCACUUUUUUAUUGGUUAUUUUAUUUUGCUUUGGUUGCUCAGAGGCAGGUGUUUUGUGACUGAGCUUUAAUUGAGGAGAACCUGUUGACUUGUAAAUUGUAAGUACUCAGUUUUCACAUAGUUUCAUUUUCCUAUUAAUCUUUGUUUUCCUUGACCUGAUUUAUAUAUGAAUUCCUAUAGCCCACCUCAGAUUCUUAAAUGAUAGUUUGAUGGGACAAUCAUGAACACGAAUAUACUGACUUUAGUUUUAAUUUACCAUUUUCUUUAAAGCUUUGUUGAUUUGUUAUAGUUUGUUCCUAUGAUUUGGUUUUGGCUCUUAUAAGUUUCCUGUUACAUUUCCAACUUUAUUUUUUUUUAGUCAUGCCACUUUUUUCUAACUUAAACUGAGAAUAACAAUAUGACAUUCAUUCCUAAGGUGAUUUUUCUUUUUUUUUUUUCCCCUCAAGUGACAGAUCUAGGAGUGAGCUUUAGGACAUAUAUACUGUGAAGGAAUUAUCUUUGCUGAUUGCUCAGUUCUUGCUUUUUUUCUUUUUUCUUUUGAGACACAGGGUCUUGCUCUGUCUCCCAGGCCAGACUACAGUGGCAUGACUACGGCCCACUGCAGCCUUGACCUCCCAGGCUCAAGCAAUCUUCCCACCUCAGAGUUCCGAGUCGCUGGGAUCACAGGUGCACAUUACCACACCUGGCUAAUAUUUUAAAUGUUUUAUAGAAAUAGGGUCUCACUGUUUUGCCAGGGCUGGUCUCGAACUCCUGGGCUCAAGCAGUCCUCACACCUUGACCUCCCAAAGUGCUGGGAUUAUAGGCAUGAGCCUUACUCAUAGUUUUAAAAGUCAAAUUGUCUUUCAUCUGUUUCCUGUCUGCACAAAAUAGCCUUCUCUUCCAUUAAUCUGCAUAUUCCCUUAGGCUUUAUUUGUUUUUGAGACAGGGUUUCACUCUAUCAUCCAGGCUGGAAUAUAGUGAUGUGAUCACAGCUUGCUGCAGCCUUCACCUCUUGGGCUCAAGGGAUCAUCCUACCUCCAUUUCCUGAGUAGCUGGGACUAUAGUCACGAGCCACCAUGCCUGGCUAAUUUUUUAAAUUUUUUGUAGAGAUGAGGGUCUCACUAUGUUGCCCAGGCUGUUCUCAAACUCCUAGGCUCAAACAGUCCUCCUGCCUCAGCCUCCCAAAGUGCUGGGAUUACAGGCAUGAAGAUCUUGCUUGCAUUUUAACUCACAAUUCAUGUAGUUAUAUAACUUCAUUUUGAAAUAGUUUCAAACUUAAAGAAAAAUUGUGAGAAAUAGCACAAGGAACUUCUUCCUGUACACCAGGGGUGUCCAAUCUUUUGGCUUCCCCAGGCCACAUUGGAAAAAGAUUGUCAUGGGCCACACGUAAAAUACACUAAUGCUAAGGAUAGCUGAUGAGCUAAAAAAAAAAAAAAACCAAAAAAAAAAUCUCAUAAUAUUUUAAGAAAGUUUACGAAUUUGUGUUUGGCUGCAUUCAAAGCCAUCCUGGGCUGCAUGUGACCCAUGGGCUGUGGGUUGGACAAGCUUGCUAUACACCGUUUGCUUAGAGUCACAAUGGCUUACAUUUAUGUAUCUUUUUAUUUUGAUAGAAUUUCAAGCUUGUAGAAGAACUGGCACAACAGUACAAGGAACUCCAGUAUACCCUUUGCUUAGAUUCAUUAGUUGCUUGCAUUUUGAUGCAUUUGCUUUAUUACACACACACAGAGUUUUCUGCACCAUUUGGAGUAGUUUGGAGUAGAAUUUUUUUUUAACUUUAGUACAUAUUUUCCAAGAACAAGGAUGUUUUCUUAGAGAAGCGCAGUAUAGUUAUUAAAAUCAGGAACUUUAAUAAUGAUACAAUGCCAUUUAUAUAUAACCUGUAUUCAUAUUCUGCCACUUGUUUUCAAUAAUGUGUCCUGUAGGUAUCUUUUUCCCCCUUAGUUUAUGAUCUAGUCCAGGAAUAAUAUCACUGAUGUGAUGAGUGUCCAUCUCAGGGCAUAUAUCAGUAGGUGCAUUGGUUUGGCCUAUGAAAAGUAAAGUAAAGUAAAGGUUCCUCUUCAAAGACUUUCCUCCCCAUGUAAUUAGGAAUAAAUAGUAACUUCUCUUAAAAGCAAAAUUAAUUCAAAGACCUGUACUAACAUUCUGAAAUAUCUGCUAGCCGUAAUAAAAAAAUUAAUGUACUUUAUGUUCUUAGCUCCCACAAUUUAGCCUAAAUAUUUGCCCUAGCAUGCUUAUACUGAAUCCAAGCAAACAUUGUCAUAGCCGUUCCUCUUCUUUAUUUAAAAGCGUUUUUACCUUUCUCAGCAUCCUGCAAGUUACUUCCUCCUUCCUUUGUUCUCCUCUACCUUUGCCUCUUUUAAAAAGUUCUGAGUUACUAUCCAAUCAGGACAGAUAUAAAAUGUAAGGUCCUGUUGCAGCCAGUGAAAACCGGACAGAGCAGUAAAGUGACCGCAUCAGGUUAUAAAUGACCCUGUCUCCUUUGUUCGGUGUACUCUCAUGGCAAAACUGCCGGCGAGUGUACGCUUUCUACAAAAAGUAAAAAAAUGACCUUGCUAAAAAAAUUAAAUUUAUAUUCAAAUACUAGUUCUUAACGGCACCAAGAAGCAAGCAUUUCAUACAGGCCCAAUGUUGGUGAAGUUAGUUUUGACUACUUCAGAUGGCAUUCAUUGGGUUUCUCCAUUGUGAAGUUACUAUUUUGUUCCUUUAUUAAUUGGUAAUUUGUGGAGAGAUACUUUGAGAUUACGCAGAUAAUCCUGUUCCUCACCAAAUUUUCACACACUGGUUUUAGCAUCCAUUGGUGUUUUUCUAACACCAUUAUUUCUUCUACAUUUAUUAGUUGCCAUUCUACUGUGAGAGCUUUUCCUUCUCCCCCAACUUAUUUGUUCAUUCAUCAUUUAGGUAUGGACUCUUUGAUUCUCAUUUUAUUUUAUGACUAUUAUCAUCAAUCUCUUGUUUAGAUUCCCAAAAUGUAUUCAGUUUGGCCAACAGAGGACUCUUCAAGCUGGCUUCUUUAUCUUUGACAUCUCAUUUUUUGAGGACUUCCAUAUUUUGUCUUAAGAAGGUGUUUCAGACUCAUAUUUUCCCUGCCUGAAUUUUAGAGUCAGCCAUUUUACCAAGGAACCCUAGUUUCUUUUCUUUGGCUAGGAGAACAGUAUUUAGAAACCCAGCUCUGGGUGCUAGAUUUUCUUAUGGUUACUGGUGGGUUUCUUACAUCUGCCUGUGUAUUCUAGGCCUUCAUAAGCAAGGAAAAAUAUGUAUAUGUGUGUAUUUCUGCAGUUUUCUAUUUUUUUUUGUGUGUGUGUUUAUGUAUAUUUUAAAACUCAAACUGUUGACUUCCCACUGACUCCUCCAUUUCCAUCCAUCAUCAUAGGAUAUAGUCUAGGCUAUACCCAAUCUUUCCAUGCUUUGUUUUCCCUCAGAAACACCAUGAAGCUGCUGAGAUCUUGUUGAAAAUUGGCACCUAAAAUCAAAAGUAUUUUAUGCGUAUUUAGUAACUGUACAAAAAUCUCCCGGUUUUAUCAACUUGACUAAUGUUUCUUGAAAUGGUAAUAUGUUUGUUUAUGGAAGGAUUAAGUAGUUUCUGUAUUAAGUAAUAGAAGCGACACCUAUUGAGCAUGUGGUAGGCAUCAGGGACUAUUGUAGACAGUUUAUAUAUAUUACAUCAGUAAUGAUAUAAUAGUGAUAACACACGCAUGCGUGCACGCACAUGCACACACACACACACAGACACACACACACACACACACAAACACAUUUUUGAGAUGGUCUUGCUCUGUUACCCAUGUUGGAGUGCAGUGGUGCAGUCAUAGCUCACUGCAGCCUUGAACUCCUGGGCACAAGUGAUCCUUCUGUCUCGGCCUUCUAAGUAGCUGGGACUGCAGGUAUGUGCCACCAUGCCUGGCUGAUUCUUAAAUUUUUUUUGUAAAGAUGAGGUCUCUCCAUGUUGCCCACGUUGGUCUCAAACUCCAGUUGUCCUCCCUCCUUGGCUUCCCAGAGUGCUGAGAUUAUAGGCAUGAGCCACUGGUCCAAACACCCACACUAUAUGAUCCUUUACUUACGUGUAAUUUUUAUUUAUGUUGAAAAGAGCACUUUCUGUUAGACUAUGACUUAUAAUGAACAUACAACUUGAUAUGAAAUUAUGAUUUGAUAUACUAAUAUUCAUUCUACAAAUGAUCCUUCUAAGGAGUAGCAAGUGAAUUAAGUAACAUUAAAUUAUAUUCCUACUGAUAUAAAUCCUAUUGAAUUGUGACCAGUAGAAUUUUACAUUUGUUGAGUGUCGUGACUUACCACCAUAACCUGUGUGGAUUUAGUCUAGAUAAUACUUACUAAAUUGAAUUAUAUAAUAUGUGUUUGGAGGUUGAAAAUAAUUCAUGAAGUUUUUCUGUGAAGAGAGUGAAUCCCUUAAGAAUAAAAAUAAUAGGAAAACCUGACUUUGUUUUCUAUAGUGCUUCACUUUUUGGUAUUUUUUUCCUUAAAAUGUUCUACAAGCUGUCAUAAGUUUCUGUCAUAUUAGUUACUGUAAGUAACUGGAAUAUUGAAAUAAAGAAAUUCUUUUUAAAAGAAGCAUUAUGUUUACUUAGUUUUAAGAAAUACAAGCAAAUGAAUACAUUAGAUCUUUUUGGCCUUGUAUUCCUGUGUUCUAAUAUUUGAAGUAGGUUUUCUCUUUUCUGAGAAUAUAUAACUUGCAACUAACUUGUGUCAUCUUGAACAAGGCAACUGCUGAGGCUCAAUUUCUUAAUGAAAUGGAGUGAUCUGUUCUGCAGUUCUUACCUCAUAAGAGAGCUCUUUAAGUUGAGUUUAGCUUCUGGAGUAUGGUCCCUGAAUCCUCAUACUUAUUAUAGUUCCUGAGGCAUAAACAAGUGAUCAGUUUUUGUUUAUUGAAUGGGGAAAACAUCACAUGAAAUCUUUUUGUAUAAGACACUUAAAAAUUUAAAUAUCCAAAUGCUAGGUAAUGCUGUUGAGUAAUUUUUUAUUGAAAGCAUUUUAAAGAGCAUUUGAGAGCACUUGUUGAAUUUAAAAUAUGAAGUGUAUUUUGAAAUACACUGUUAAUAAAGGUAAUUUUACACUGUUUGGCUGCUAUUUACAGUUUGAAGACCAAUUAAUAUGAAAUAAUUCUUUAUGAUUUUAAAGGUCUUUAGUUUUAUGAAUUUAUUAUAACCAAGUUGAAAGUAAUUUUUAAACAGUUUAUUGAAAAUACAGUAACCAUUUAAGAGACUGGUUUUCUGGAGCAAAGACUAUCUCUGGGACCUGAAACCAUUCUUUGAAAUUCUUUCCCUGGUGUGCCUGAGUCUUUCUUAACUUGGUGGUUCCAUGUUGAAGGAGUUGUUAAAUGCAGCCCCGGGGGCGGGGGAUGGGUGGGGUGGUGGGGGAAGUUCUGAACUGUAGUUUAAAAAGCUUUCACAAACAUUUUGGUUACUCAGUUUGGAUGGUGUUCUUUAAGUGAGUUUUAUUGACUCAUGGAAUCAUUGAUGACAGAUUAAUAAUUUAAGGUUCAAGUCUGGCAUUGCUAUAGAGAAAUACCUGAGCAUUUGGCAGGCCAAGGUGGGCGGAUCAGGAGGUGAGGAGAUCAAGACCAUCUUGGCCAACAUGGUGAAACCCCAUCUCUACUAAAAUACAAAAAAUUAGCCAGGCGUGGUGGUGCGUGCUACUUGGGAGGCUGAGGCAGGUGAAUUGCUUGAACCCGGGAGGCGGAGCUUGCAGUGAGCUGAGAUUGCGCCACUGCACUCCACCCUGGUGACAGAGCAAGAGUCUGUCUCAAAAAAAAAAAGAAAAAGAAAAAGAAAAAAAAAAGAAAUACCUGAGCCUGGGUAAUUUUUAAAGAAAAUAGGCUUGUUUGGCUCAUGGUUCUUCAGGCUUUACAGGAAGUGGGGUACUGACAUCUGUUUGGCUUCUGGCGAGGCCCCAAGAAGCUUUUACUCAUGCUGGAAGGUGACUCGGGAAGAAGCAGGUUACAUGGCCAAAGCAGGAGCCAGAGAGCGUAGGGGGAGGUGCUGUAUACUUUUAAAAUACCGUAUCGCAGGAGAACUCACUCCCUAUCAUGAGGACAGCACCAAGACAGGAGAGAUCCACUUCCACGAUCCAAUCACUGCCUGCAAUUGGGGAUUACAGUUCAACAUGGGAUUUGGGAUGUGACAAUAUUAAAACUAUAUCAGUAACCCUCCAAGCACUUUAGAGCCUAUACCAUUACUAUGAUUUGAUGAUGACAGUAUAUUUUCAAGAAUUGAUUAAACUUUCUCUGGUUCAUUCAGAAAAGUAGGGAUAGAAUAAUUUGCUCCAGUAAAUGAAAUUAAACUAUAGUAUCAUUUUUUAAGUGUGCAUUUCUCAGGGGUCUCAGACUUUUUUUGUUAUGGUUUCUUCUUACAAUAUUUUUAGUAGUGCAUAAGAUUUAUGAAUAAGAUUGAAAUAUCCCUUUAUUGUAUGGGAAAUCCAGAACAAGUAAUUUACUCUUUCUCAGUCUGUUUUUAUUUUUAUGGUGCAGGUAAUACUUUGCAUCCUGCCUCUAUUCCUAUGGUACUUAAGAAAUUGUAUGAAAUGAUGUUAAAGUGCUUUGAAAACUUAUGGAUAAUACUUUAGCUAUUUUGUUUUAUAUAGCUUUCACUUGUGUUCAUCCGUAGAUAAAAUUAGCAUUUUGGACUUUGGAAAGAUGCCAUUUUAUAAGUCCAAAAACUUUGUAGUUAACCUGUGUAUGUCUUUGUAAAUAAGUAAAUAUGCUUAGAUUUUUUGAAAGUUCUUAAAGGAAUCAUUGAGAUAAUUUGAAUUAAUGACUUUAUUUUGCAGGUGAAAAAACCAAAGCCAGAAAAGAUAAUGACUUAAAAUCAUAUAGUGUGACAAGGCCAGUUUUGCAUUCCACAGUACAUUAAUAUAUGGAAAGAGUACAUUUGAUAUGAGCUCAUGUUUUGGUUUAUGGUAUAUUCAUGGAAGGGAACAGAUACAGAUCAUCUGAAGCGAUGAGUAGUCCCCAGUUGUGCAUUUUUGCUUUGGAAUAUUCUUAUAUUCGAAUAUUGUUCUUUAUAAAUUCAUAGCUUUUCAAAUAAAAUAAGCCCCACUAUGAAAUCCUGACCCAGGAGGAGCUGAAAAUGUGUGUUGUUUUUUUCAAUCAUGCUUCCCUGUUGAUCUUAGUACACAUCCUAAGAACUAUUGGCAGUUAAUGAACAUAUUUUUGUUUAUAGACUUUUCCUGAGUUAGAGGAGGUGAACAACUUGUUUUAAAGGUUUUUCUAGGCUGCAGUUCCCAUAAGGAUAUAUAUUUUAAAAAGUGUUAAGGAUGGUUAGUGUAGCACUUCUGUUUCUUGAAAAAUCCAGAUAAUACUAAGCAGUAAUCCUUAAAUCUGAGGCCAUUAUUCCCUGAGGAUUAAUUUUGUUAGCUGAAAGAUAUGUGGAUCUUUGCAUGUAGAGGGUGUUGGUAAUAGGCAGUUGUGUUUAGGGAGAUACGUGUGGUAAUAUAGGUUUGAAAAAGUCUUGUGUUGAGUAAAAGGGAGAGGAGGAAAGGCUUUGGGGAUCCAUAAAGUCCUAUAACUUUCAAAAUAAUAAAAUUUCAGCUAGAUGAACCUCAUAUCUUGUCCUUUAAAGUUUUAUAUAUUACUUUAUCACUUCAAAUAUUAUACGCUAAAACUGUCAUAGAACUACCAUCUACUGUUUCUCUAUCUUGGAGUUCACACUGUUUCCAAGCCAAGUGGAAUAUGAAAAUUAAAAGGAUGUGGAGGAAGUUGGAAGCUACAUCUGUGAAUAUAGGCAUCUUAAAACUCACCAUGUAUCAAAAUGUGUAAUGUGGAUGUUUCCAAGAGAGCUUCUUUUUAAAAAAUUAUAUGUAGUAUUGAAUUGGAGGGGUAGGGGAAGAAAGAUAGUCAAGAGAAUAUAGAAGAAAACAUAUACUUCAUGUACUUCGACUUUGCUGUAGCCGUUGGGAGCAUUGAAAUUUGACAGGACUUUCCAAAGUAGAAAACUAUAACUUUCAUGUGUUUUUACACUUAGUCAACAGUUGUUUCUUAGAUGUUCGCUAAGACCAUGCAACUGUGAUAAAUAUAUUAAAUAUAAGAUGUUAUUUUUCUCUUCAGUGAGUUUAUAGUCUGGACAGAAAAGAUAGGUGGAACCAAAGAAAACUUUACAAGACAAUUUUUGCUAAAUUAUGUAACAAAUGCUCUAUUAGAGGAAAAAGUAUUAGCCAGGGCAAAAGUUAGCUAGUGAGAUGGAAUUAAACCAAAGAGUUUUGGUAUCUGACUGCUGUCUUAGCCCAGGUAAGCUCAUCCUUCCUUCUGAGACUCCCUGUGAGCACGGAAGGGCAGCUACUCUUAAUUUAAGCCCUUCAGCACAGUUGAUGGCCCAGAGCAUGGCAGAAGAUAACUGUGUUGUCUUUUCUUCGCUUUAACUUCUCUCUUGCAGUCAUCUUAUGUGUGAAUGUAAGUUUUCUUCCACAGACUUCUGUAUGUACUGUCCUUGACUGUUUUUCUUUUAGACACCUCUCACUUCAGGAUUUCCAUUUCCACUCUCUUUAGUUCCUCUUUAAGGAGGUCAGUAGGCGAUAGCUUUGCUAGAUUUGAGAAGCAGUGUUUUUUUGUUUCCCCUUUCCAGUCUUCUGUGCUUAAAAAUGAAAGUUUAGAAUGUGCCCUUUCUGUCACAGAAAUGAAAGAAAGUUGGUAUUAUUGGACCAGCUAUAUGUUAGAAACUUUAUAUUCAGUGUACUAUUUAAUCAUCACAAAUUUAUGAUGUAAUUAUUUUCAUUUUAUAGAUAAAGAAACUGGAGAUCCCCCAUUAAGUAAUUUGCCUGAGGCUGCACGACCAAUAAAUGACAUCAGAUGCUCACCCCGGCCCGCCCCCUGCUGCUUCAUUCUUCCUUUGAAGCUGAGAGUACUAAAAGGAAAAAGAAAAAAUGGGAGAUUGUAGGAGACAGCUGAAUUGAACAUCUUUUCAGCUAAAAGUUAAUGAAAAGUUUAGUUUUGAAUUAUGCGUCAGGAGCCUCUGAGCAAAUUGUUCUGUGUCAGAGGGUUUCAUAGCUUCACAGACAGGAUUUGAGUUGUGUUUCAGUUAUUCAAGGUCUGUGAGCUUCUCAUAUGAUCUUGUGACUCUUCAUAGAAGUAUGGUAAAGAACUAGAGCACAGUGCUAGGUAUAUAGUAGGCACAUAGGAAAUUGCUGCUAUAUGUUAUCACUACUUAAACAAAAUUUAAGAUUUGUAUUCAUCAUUGAAUAUAGAGUAAAGUAGAUGCUCUUUGCAGCUUUUGGCAAGUGAGUAGUGAACCUUAGUUUAGCCAUUUAUUUUCUUUAAUAAUUCUUUAUUUAUAUUUCAUCAUAUCUCUUUAUCAGCCCCAUCACUGAGAAGAAUUUUUUCACUGUAUAGUUGCCUCUGCACUUAAAGCAGGCUUGGUCCAUGAAUCCCAUGACAAGAGCUUUGAGGACAUGAGGAGCAUUCUUUGUUCAAACAUACUGUGUUUUCCUUUGGAUCACUGGUGAGUAAGCUUCCCUCUAGAGCUGGGUGAGCUUAGUCCUCAGUUUUGCAGAGAAAGGAGCAGCAAGGAGCAGUUGACUGCUUCCCUCUGGGUGCUAGGAGGAAAGGAAAGUGAGUCAGCAUUCAUUUUGUUCUCCUCCCACCUUGCAACAUCUGUCUGCCAUUGGUCUGCUUCCUACCUCCUUUAACUUGUCAGUGCUUAAUCCUCCAGAAGGCAUCCUUAAACUGCCUAAGAGACACCAUAAUAUUGUAUGGGGCCUUUGACAGUUCUUUCCUAAAUAGAUUUAAGUCACAAUUCUAAAUUUUGGAAUAAUAGCAAGAAACGUUUGGAACACUUUGCAGAUAGUUUCAGGUGUGUAUAUGUGAGUGUACCCUUUAUUUUCUCUGCAGCCCUUACCUAACACACAGCAGAGAGAAAAAUACCAAGGAAUGAAAUUGUGUUUUAUGAGUAAACAUGAUGACUUCCUUCUCAAACAGACAUAACUCUGUAACUGCUUAAGUUGUUGAACCUUUUAUUCUGUUCUUACACUUGAUCUUUUUCUAUAUUUACCUUUUUCGUCUUUCUCUCAAAUUCCUUAUUUUGGUUUUAUUGUUCAGUGCAGGACUUGAACACUCCUAAAAUUGUUUCUUCUUUGUGGAAAAGAAAAUGGCAGGAGUGAGGCAGUAAAAAUUGUGACUGAAGUAACAGAAAUGCCAAGGCAUGGACAGCAGCCAUUACUAGAUAACUAAAACUUGAUUAUAUUGAAUUAUAGAUUUGACCAAUGCUGAAAUAGCAUGGAAAUUAGAGCUCUGAGGGACCUUAGGAGCUGCAGAAUAUAGCCUUUUUAUUUCACAGGUGAGGAAACGACAUUUUGGGGAUUUGGCCGGAUCAAUACAGCAAAGUUAUCUGUGGAACCGUGGCUACACCUUGGUCUCUUGACUUGUAUUUGACUUUUCCAUGAUUGAAAUGAGAUUAUCUUAGAAGUAACAAAUGGCAGACACUGAUGACCUAAUGCUACACUGGGUUUUUAUUAGUGUUUAUUUUACUUUCAUAAAAAAAAUUGUACAUUUCAAGUUAGGAUUAUUAUUGAAUUAUCACAGUAUUCACUACAGACGUCGAUUUACGAGCUUCUCAAGUGUACAUCAAUUAUAAUCAAUUCUAAUAUUGAUUAUAUUGAUUAUUCAUAGUCUAACAUUGGGGGAAUUGGUUACAUCCUGCUGUAUCCAUGUGGUAGAAUAUCAUACUUCUGGAUUUGGAAAGAAUGUCUCAUGGUAUUAGGAAAUGCUUAUUAAGUGAAAGUCCUGAACAAUAUAUACAGUAUAAUACCAGUCAUAUGUUUAAAAAAACGAAGUAUAUAGUUCCUUAAAAGUUAAUAAUGACAGUGGUUCUUUGAAUGCUAGCAUUAUGAAAAUUUUAAUUUUACUUUAUUUUCAUGUUUUCUGCAAAGGCACAUUAUCAUCAAAUCAGUGAGUAUAAUAAAAAGGCAUUUAUUGCUGUAAACUUCCCUUUUAGAACUGCUUUUGAUGCAUCUCAUAAGUUAUGGAUUAAUUUAUUUUUGGAAAUCAAGUGCAAUAUUGGAAGCCAUUUCUACUAAUUUUAUUUCACUUUUAAAUUUAUGAUUUGAUUUGAAUACUAUCAUGGGAGGAGCUGUGAGUGCUGGGGAAGAUAAUGAUGACUUAAUUGAUAAUUUAAAAGAAGCUCAGUAUAUUCGUACUGAAAGAGUGGAGCAAGCCUUCAGAGCGAUUGAUCGUGGAGAUUACUAUUUGGAAGGCUACAGAGACAAUGCUUACAAAGACUUAGCCUGGAAGCAUGGAAACAUCCACUUGUCAGCACCUUGCAUUUAUUCUGAAGUUAUGGAAGCAUUGAAACUUCAACCAGGAUUGUCUUUUCUUAACCUGGGAAGUGGAACCGGAUAUUUAAGUACAAUGGUGGGCUUAAUUUUAGGUCCUUUUGGAAUAAAUCAUGGGAUUGAGCUUCAUUCAGAUGUGGUGGAAUAUGCCAAGGAAAAACUGGAGAGCUUCAUCAAAAAUAGUGAUAGCUUUGAUAAAUUUGAGUUCUGUGAACCUGCAUUUGUUGUUGGUAAUUGCCUCCAGAUAGCUUCUGACAGUCAUCAGUAUGAUCGAAUUUAUUGUGGAGCUGGAGUGCAGAAAGACCAUGAAAACUACAUGAAAAUAUUACUAAAAGUUGGAGGCAUAUUAGUCAUGCCUAUAGAGGAUCAGUUAACACAGAUUAUGCGAACUGGACAGAACACUUGGGAAAGUAAAAAUAUCCUUGCUGUUUCAUUUGCUCCACUUGUGCAACCAAGUAAGAAUGAUAAUGGCAAACCAGAUUCUGUGGGACUCCCUCCCUGUGCUGUCAGGAAUCUACAGGACUUGGCUCGUAUUUACAUUCGACGCACACUUAGAAAUUUCAUAAAUGAUGAGAUGCAGGCCAAGGGGAUUCCUCAAAGGGCUCCACCCAAAAGGAAAAGAAAGAGAGUUAAACAGAGAAUUAACACUUACGUAUUUGUGGGUAAUCAGCUUAUUCCUCAGCCUCUAGACAGUGAAGAGGAUGAAAAAAUGGAAGAGGAUAACAAAGAAGAGGAGGAAAAAGAUCACAAUGAAGCAAUGAAGCCAGAGGAGCCACCUCAAAAUUUACUGAGAGAAAAAAUCAUGAAGCUGCCCCUCCCUGAAUCUUUAAAAGCUUACUUGACAUAUUUUAGAGACAAAUAACUUAGAUCAAGAAGAAAAAUGCCUACUGAUAAUUCCUUUAGUCUUGAAAAUGUAGCAUUUGUUAGGAGUUAAAAGAGAGAAUUAUUUCUUUCAUCAGAGCAAAUUAUAGUGGAAAAAAAAUCACUUGUUUCUGUCAGUAACACAAAUGAUGUAUUCAGUGAAUAAAAGAAUCCCUUUUAUAAAAUCUAUUUUUCUUUAAAUCUUGGAAAAAUGUUGUUUUAGCUCAGAGUGAUUUCAAAGUGGAAUGCAACAGUAGUCAAGACUUGUGUACUAUAAAUCCUUUUCUGAUUCCUUACAGAUUUGUAGUGAUGAGGUUUAGAUUUAAUUUUAUAUAUGGUUUAAAUAAUUGUUAAGCUUAUAUAACCUGAUCUGAAUUGCAGUUGUUUGCAUUUCCUCUAUGAAAACUUCAUUUAUCUAAUAAGGAAGUCAAAUGCUUUGUAGACUAUUUACCUUACUUUUGUUGCAAUCACUGUUGUUGGGUUGCUGUAUAUAUAUUCCGGGCAAUAUAUGAGUGCAAUAACAAUACAAGAUAUUGAAUAAUUUAGCUUUAAAAAAUCCCACAAAUUUUAUGAAAUUUUACAGCCCUGCUACUUUUGCUUUUGAAUCUCUUGCCAAAAGACAUGGGUAAAAUAUCUGCCUCUCUCAUAGAGAUUUUAAGAGCACAGCAAGUGAAUUAUUAAAACAAAGUCUAUACUUAAUACAACUCUUUAUAUGGACCCUUUACAUUUUCAGUAUUUAAAAAAAUGAGGUUAUCUUAACUCUAUAGAAUUUUAAAAGUAUAUUUAGAAUUGUUUUUUCUGUAGUUCACUGUAUAAAGUAUUUGGUUUUUUAAAAAAAGCAAAACCAUUGUUAUGUGUGACUCUUGAUAGGACACAGAACGAGUGAAUGAGCAUGAGUGAGGCCACUUUCUUGGAUGGCUGUAAGUAGCAGGGCCAGGGUAGACCUGGUCAGCGGAUGCACUUUAGCAGAUGGAACUUCUAGUUUAUCUGAAUAUUUAUCUUUGACAAGGUAGGGCUGAGCCUACAUUUGCUUUUGAUCUAUCUAGUAUAAGAAAUAUUCACAGAAAUUGUAUGUAGAUACCCUUUGUUUUGAAAAUGCUGUUCAGAAUCAUAGUGUAAUCUUUGGGACCUAUGCCAUGUUCAUUUCACUCCUUCCCAUAUUUUUUGUGUUUCUUUUGGUAAAACUAUAAUGGUUUUCAUUUUUUACUUAAUAUCACACAGUUAAACUGUCCAUAUUUGAGCUUUAUUUUAGCUUAUCAGUGAUAAAAAACAGGUAGUAACUGCCAUUGUUUGUUUGUUUUCCUAAUAAGGCCUGAAAACAGCCAUUCCUUGUUAAGAAAGUGUACAAUGUAACAUAUUUGCUAGAGUUACAUGGAUUAUAUAUUUCUUAAAGGGAAAAAUUUGAGAGUAUCAUGGACUACCACCAGCAUUAUUAUUACAGUAGUUACUCAGAUUUGGUUAAGGAAGCCCAAGCAAUGUAUAGUGAAAGGAUUAUUAUCUCUCUGCUAAGAUUCAGAUAUUGUUUCAGAAAUCUCAGCUCCAGUAAUUCCACAACAUCUAAAAACAAAUGUUUGUGAUCAUGUGUAAGCAUGAAAUUGUUCCAAGUAAGUGAGGAUAUUUUAGUUAUGUGAAAGACAGUUUCAUGGAAGGUAUUUGUUUUAUACCAGUGGCUGGGAUGGUGGAAUUGGGGUUAUUUCUACAAUUAUUCUUAGACGAUUACUAAACUGUUAAGAAAUGCCCCAUAUCAUUUUUGUAUCUAGGAAAGAAAAAAAUCAGUUUCAUACUGUUGUCAUCUGUCAGAAAUGCUCAUUUUAUUUUGAAUUAAAUGUGGCUUUUGAAGUACCUAGUUACCUUGAAUUCCUGGUGACCACAUGUUUUUAUCUGGAAAACCUGGAGAAAGUUAUCUGUCCCAUCUCCCCUGCUUGUUUUUUUUUUUUUUUUUGGUUGGAGCUGCUGUUUAGAUGAUGCUUUUACUAUGCAGGAGAGAGUUUUUGUUAAGGAUAUAUUUGAAGAUUGGCUUUUCCAUAUUGUCCUUCAUUCUUUGACCAUGGCAAAGUGUACAGUAGAUUUUCAUGAUCAUUGCAUAUUUCUUGUCAUUGAAAUGUAUCUUUUAUGUUUUUAAAUGCAUUCAUUUUACACUUGUGAGUUUAUCAUUGACUUUAAGAGGUAGAAAUGAAAAAUGAAAAUUAAAGCUAAAGCCUUUUUAUCUAUUAAUGCAGAUAUAUUAGAAUAAGAAUAUUUUGGGUUUGUGUUUAUUUUUUAAUGAAUUUAUGUUUACUUGAUAUGGAAAAUUACGCUUUAUAGGUGGAAAAGUAGCAAAUAAAGAUUAAGUAAAAGUAAGUGAAAAUGAUGGGGAAUAUAGUAUUGGAAUUUUAUAGCUAGUUAAAACAGUAAGUAUCAUCUAAUUUGGGUGUUUAUUUUGCAGAUGAGAAAACAGACCUAGAACCGUGGCAUGUUUUGCCUGAAACAUACAGUGAGUUAGAGACAGGGCCUAAGAUAGCUUCUAGCAUCAGAUCAAUCCCAAGAAUCCAUCAGCAACCUCAGACCAACCCAAGAAGAUAAUUUAAAUCUAUACUGCUUAUUGGUCAAUAUAUUUGGUUCUAGUAUUAAUAAAGAAAAAUGUUAUUAAAAUAGCAUACAUAGUAGUAAAAUAAAAUACAAAAAGUGUGUUGAUUUAUAGCUGUUUGAGAUGAUAAAAGUGAAGCAAAGCCUGUUAAAUCAUUGGAAGACUUGGAAAAUUAUUUUAAAUAAACAAUUACAUGUAAUUAA